GAACUGACAGACUCAGUCACUGAAGAGGGAAAAGGAGUGAGAAGACAAAGCCGUCAAAGCCCCAACAGCUUUGUAUUUCUCCAGCCCGGCGCAGACCCCGGAGCUCCCGAGGCACUCCCUCCAUCUUUGGAACACGCCAGUAAUUGAUUGAUAACAGGAAGCUAUGAGGGACCCUGUGAGUAGCCAGUACAGUUCCUUUCUUUUCUGGAGGAUGCCCAUCCCAGAACUGGAUCUGUCGGAGCUGGAAGGCCUGGGUCUGUCAGAUACAGCCACCUACAAGGUCAAAGACAGCAGCGUUGGCAAAAUGAUCGGGCAAGCAACUGCAGCAGACCAGGAGAAAAACCCUGAAGGUGAUGGCCUCCUUGAGUACAGCACCUUCAACUUCUGGAGAGCUCCCAUUGCCAGCAUCCACUCCUUCGAACUGGACUUGCUCUAAGGCCAAGACUUCUCUCUCCCAUCACCUUGCCCUCAUUGUCUUCCCUCUCAAGCCCCUUCCUUUCCACUCCUUUCCCAUUUUAAUCUUGUUCUCUCCCUACUGUGUUGGUGGUGCUGAUGAAUCUGCCAGAGUUGAGUUCUAUGUAUUUAUUUAUCUAUCUGUCUACUCCAUUUCUCUCAAAAGCCCUCAAGUCACAAAGUAAAUGGUUCAAGCAAUGGAGUACUGGGUCACAGGGAUUCCUCCUUUCCCCCCCAAAUAUUAACUCCAGAAACUAGGCCUGACUGGGGACACCUGAGAGUAGUAUAGUAGUGCAAAAUGGAAGACUGAUUUUUGACUCUAUUAUAAUCAGCUUCAGAGAUUCCUUAAACCUUCCUAAUUUCCUGCUCCAGGGCAGUAAACACAAAUAUUUCUUCAAGGGGUGAUGAAAACCUCGGAAGUUUUAAUUUGAGGUUAUCUGCUACGAAACAGUAUUUCUAAAAGGCUAAAGUGAUAAGUCUCUUGCUUUUUUUUGAUCCUGCUCUUAUAUUCUUUUUUUUCCUCAGAGAAAUCAGGAGGGUAGUUAGAGGUAUAAAACAGGAGGAAAUAUUAUGGAAAAUGAAAAUAGGGAAAAUAAUUGAAUCAUUUUAGAAGUAGCUAAUUUCUUUUCUCAAAAGAGUGUCCCUUCUUCACACCUACUCACUUUACAACUUUGCUCCUAACUGUGGGUUGAAAACUCUAGCUAAAGAAAGUUAUCAAAUCUUAACAUGCAUUCCUACUAUUAUGAUAGUUUUUAAGGUUUCAAUUCAAUCUUCUGAACGGCAUAAGUCCUAUUUUAGCCUUACCUCCUGCAUUUGCAAUACGUAAUACUGAUCAGUGGGCACAGUUCUUCAGCUACAUUGAGACCCUGAAAUGAACAAUUAUAUUCUGACUCGACAUCUUGUCCCCAAUCCUUCCAAAAAUAUUGAUGGUGAUUUGUGCUACCAUUUACUCGUUUAUUUAAUAAAGACAUUCAAUCCCAGGACUGGAGUCUAAUUUUCUCUCUUCACAAGAAAAGCCACAGAAAUCUGAGAAAUUAGCCUUGCUUUCACACUUAGCUUAUACAUCUUUUUUUUCUUUUUUAUUUUUGAGACAGGGUCCCACUCUGUCACCCAGGCUGGAGUGCAGUGGCGGGGAUCACCGCUCACUGCAACCUCCACCCACCAGGGUCAAGGGAUCCUCCCACCUCAGGCUCCCAGGUAGCUGGGAUUACAGGCGCCUGCCACCAGGCCUGGUUAAUUUUUGUAUUUUUCAUAGAGACGGGGUUUCACCAUGUUGGCCAGGCUGGUCUCUAACUCCUGACCUCAGGUGAUCUGCCCGCCUUAGCCUCUCAAAGUGCUGAGAUUACAGGCGUGAGCCACUGAGCCCGGCCUCAUUUUAUCUUUCUAUAAUAAUAUUCAACUUAGAGGAAGAAUGAUUUGAGUAGCAUUUAGACAUUAGAUGGUGAACUUCGCAUUGAACAGAUAAUGAAAGGGCAAAAUCAACUUAAAAUUAGAAAAGUAGUUAGGGAGACAGGUACAACCACUCUUCUGCUUGCCCACUGACUACCAACAUUAUAUUUCAGGUAAUAAUUCUCCUAGGUGCCUAAGAAGAUAAACGAAUUCACUCAAAUAUGUUAUCUGCUUAACUUCUGGUUUUUGUGUGCCUGCUAUAGGAAAGCACUGAGCCAAACAGAAUGUAAACGGGAAUGAGACAAGACUCCAACUCUCAAAAGAGAAACUGUAAAUACCAAUAUGGAUAGGACAGAAUUGGGCAGUGUACUAUAAAUAAGGAUGACACUAUACCCUAAAUAAGGAUGAUCUAGAGAAGUCCCCAGGUGGGAGAAAAAAAGACAAAUCCUCCCUCUAGGCCAUGAAAAGCCCACAUCUAAAGACGGUCCCAGUCUAACGAAGAAUGGGGCCAGGAAGGAUAAGUAGUGCGUCCUUUUCUAUUUUUACUGAGUUUUGAAGGGCCCCUUCAGAGUCCUUCAGCCAUGGCAAUUGGUGGGUGGAGACAGGGAUCAACUGUUUGGUAAAUAAAGUGACUAAAUGGA